CCCGCCAUGGCUCUGAGGCGCGCCCUGCCCGCGCUGCGCCCCUGCAUUCCCCGCUUCGUCCCGCUGUCCACGGCGCCGGCCUCCCGCGAGCAGCCCGCAGCGGGCCCAGCGGCCGUGCCAGGAGGUGGGUCGGCCACGGCAGUGCGGCCGCCGGUGCCCGCCGUGGACUUCGGCAACGCGCAGGAGGCGUACCGCAGCCGGCGAACCUGGGAGCUGGCGCGGAGCCUGCUGGUGCUGCGCUUGUGCGCCUGGCCCGCGCUGCUGGCGCGCCACGAGCAGCUGCUGUAUGUUUCCAGGAAACUUCUAGGACAGAGGCUAUUCAACAAGCUCAUGAAGAUGACCUUCUAUGGGCAUUUUGUAGCCGGGGAGGACCAGGAGUCCAUCCAGCCCCUGCUUCGGCACUACAGGGCCUUCGGUGUCAGCGCCAUCCUGGACUAUGGAGUGGAGGAGGACCUGAGCCCCGAGGAGGCAGAGCACAAGGAGAUGGAGUCCUGCACCUCAGCUGCGGAGAGGGAUGGCAGUGGCACGAAUAAGCGGGACAAGCAAUACCAGGCCCACUGGGCCUUCGGGGACCGCAGGAAUGGUGUCAUCAGUGCCCGCACCUACUUCUACGCCAAUGAGGCCAAGUGCGACAGCCACAUGGAGACAUUCUUGCGCUGCAUCGAAGCCUCAGGUAGAGUCAGCGAUGACGGCUUCAUAGCCAUUAAGCUCACAGCACUGGGGAGACCCCAGUUUCUGCUGCAGUUCUCAGAGGUGCUGGCCAAGUGGAGGUGCUUCUUUCACCAAAUGGCUGUGGAGCAAGGGCAGGCGGGCCUGGCUGCCAUGGACACCAAGCUGGAGGUGGCGGUGCUGCAGGAAAGUGUCGCAAAGUUGGGCAUCGCAUCCAGGGCUGAGAUUGAGGACUGGUUCACGGCAGAGACCCUGGGAGUGUCUGGCACCAUGGACCUGCUGGACUGGAGCAGCCUCAUCGACAGCAGGACCAAGCUGUCCAAGCACUUGGUAGUCCCCAACGCACAGACAGGACAGCUGGAGCCCCUGCUGUCCCGGUUCACUGAGGAGGAGGAGCUACAGAUGACCAGGAUGCUACAGCGGAUGGAUGUCCUGGCCAAGAAAGCCACAGAGAUGGGCGUGCGGCUGAUGGUGGAUGCCGAGCAGACCUACUUCCAGCCGGCCAUCAGCCGCCUGACGCUGGAGAUGCAGCGGAAGUUCAAUGUGGAGAAGCCGCUCAUCUUCAACACAUACCAGUGCUACCUCAAGGAUGCCUAUGACAAUGUGACCCUGGACGUGGAGCUGGCUCGCCGUGAGGGCUGGUGUUUUGGGGCCAAGCUGGUGCGGGGCGCAUACCUGGCCCAGGAGCGAGCCCGUGCGGCAGAGAUCGGCUAUGAGGACCCCAUCAACCCCACGUACGAGGCCACCAACGCCAUGUACCACAGGUGCCUGGACUACGUGUUGGAGGAGCUGAAGCACAACGCCAAGGCCAAGGUGAUGGUGGCCUCCCACAAUGAGGACACAGUGCGCUUUGCACUGCGCAGGAUGGAGGAGCUGGGCCUGCAUCCUGCUGACCACCGGGUGUACUUUGGACAGCUGCUAGGCAUGUGUGACCAGAUCAGCUUCCCGCUGGGCCAGGCCGGCUACCCCGUGUACAAGUACGUGCCCUAUGGCCCCGUGAUGGAGGUGCUGCCCUACUUGUCCCGCCGUGCCCUGGAGAACAGCAGCCUCAUGAAGGGCACCCAUCGGGAGCGGCAGCUGCUGUGGCUGGAGCUCUUGAGGCGGCUCCGAACUGGCAACCUCUUCCAUCGCCCUGCCUAGCACCCGCCAGCACACCCUUAGCCUCCAGCACCCCCCGCCCCCGCCCAGGCCAUCACCACAGCUGCAGCCAACCCCAUCCUCACACAGAUUCACCUUUUUUCACCCCACACUUGCAGAGCUGCUGGAGGUGAGGUCAGGUGCCUCCCAGCCCUGCCCAGAGUAUGGGCACUCAGGUGUGGGCCGAACCUGAUACCUGCCUGGGACAGCCACUGGAAACUUUUGGGAACUCUCCUCGAAUGUGUGGGCCCAAGGCCCCCACCUCUGUGACCCCCAUGUCCUUGGACCUAGAGGAUUGUCCACCUUCUGCCAAGGCCAGCCCACACAGCCCGAGCCCCUUGGGGAGCAGUGGCCGGGCUGGGGAGGCCUGCCUGGUCAAUAAACCACUGUUCCUGCA